GAAAUCCGGUUCUAACCGGUCCGGGGCUCCCAGCGCUAUAAAAACUUUAUAAACCCCCCGGAGCCCGAGCAGUGUGAAGAAGAGGCGAGAACGACCCCCGGACCGACCAAAGCCCGCGCGCCGCUGCAUCCCGCGUCCAGCACCUACGUCCCGCUGCCGUCGCCGCCGCCACCAUGCCCAAGAGAAAGGCUGAAGGGGAUGCUAAGGGAGAUAAAGCAAAGGUGAAGGACGAACCACAGAGAAGAUCCGCGAGGUUGUCUGCUAAACCUGCUCCUCCAAAGCCAGAGCCCAAGCCUAAAAAGGCCCCUGCAAAGAAGGGAGAGAAGGUACCCAAAGGGAAAAAGGGAAAAGCUGAUGCUGGCAAGGAGGGGAAUAACCCUGCAGAAAAUGGAGAUGCCAAAACAGACCAGGCACAGAAAGCUGAAGGUGCUGGAGAUGCCAAGUGAAGUGUGUGCAUUUUUGAUAACUGUGUACUUCUGGUGACUGUACAGUUUGAAAUACUAUUUUUUAUCAAGUUUUAUAAAAAUGCAGAAUUUUGUUUUACUUUUUUUUUUUUUUUAAAAGCUAUGUUGUUAGCACACAGAACACUUCAUUGUUGUUUUUGGGGGAAGGGGCAUAUGUCACUAAUAGAAUGUCUCCAAAGCUGGAUUGAUGUGGAGAAAACACCUUUCCCUUCUAGUUUUGAGAGACUUCCUCUUGGCUCCCAGGAGGAGGGAUUCCCUGACUUUGACACACAUGGCCACCUUGGCACAAAAGCCUUGUGGUAUAGAAAAACAAAUUUGUUUUUAUGUCCUCUUCUCCCUUUCCAUCGUUCAGCAUAGACUUAACUCCCUUAAGCCCAGACAUCUGUUGAGACCUGACCCCUAGUCAUUGGUUACCAGUGUGUCAGGCAAUCUGGACUUUCCAGUGAUGCCACUGAGAUGGCACCUGUCAAAAGAGCAGUGGUUCCAUUUCUAGAUUGUGGAUCUUCAGAUAAAUUCUGCCAUUUUCAUUUCACUUCCUGAAAGUCAGGGUCGGCUUGUGAAAAGUUGUUAAACAACAUGCUAAAUGUGAAAUGUCAACCCUCACUCUAAACUUUCCCUGUUCAGAGCAUCAGAUGAAGACUUCAUUGGGUUUUAUAGUGGCUUUCUGAUUUUUGGUAGUCCAUUGAAGAAGGGAGUUUGAAAGUUGUUGUAUACUGUUAACGAUUGUCUGCCCAUGUCCUGCCUGAAAUACCAUGAUUGUUUAUGGAAAGUAUCUUUAAUAAAGCUGGAUACAGUUUGGCUUGGAAUGCUGCCUCUGAUCUUUUCCCACAAGUGGGGUAACCUGGUUUAUCCAAGUCUCUUGGAACAGGGUACGUUCUGCUUUGAGGUACUCCAUGUACAGUCUAAUGAUGAUCUUUCACUGAUUUAUAGUCAGCUUCCAAAACACACAGUGCUAGGUGCAGUUAGGAAGGAUUCCAGGAGUAGACUUAGCUGAUGGUGAAAGGCUGGGAGUAUGGAGUGAUUUCUGUACUUGGUUAUGCAGCAUUCCCUGCAGUGUUUGUUUUUUGCAUGACUCCGAAUACAUGAAGUGUAUUAAAUGCAGAUUUUUGGUAGAUCUGCGGUUUUGGCUGGGUAGCUGACAGGAGCCUCUCUACUUCCAUCUGCAUUUGCAACUUCUAUAAAAUUAGCAAAUUAAUAGACUCAUGUCAGAGAGUGUCUCUGUGAAUGUGUACACAGUUGUCCAUUUGUAAGGUAGAUGACACUUUGCUCCUAAGUAGACCUGCAAACAAAGACAAUGGGGUCUUUCCUGAUUCCUUUAGUUUGGAGAUGCAGAGAACCCCACGUUUCUCUAAGUGAAAUGGCAAGAAGUUAUUUGUUAGAAUAUGGAACUGGUAACAAAUUCAUGUUUGCACCUUGAAUUUGCUUUCACAGACCUGGCUGUAUUGUUGGACAGGAAUAAAGUAAAUUGGAGACUAA